CUUGACGCUGUGGCCCGGAAGUGGAGCGGCUGUCGCAGUGCGGCUCCGGCAGUGGCAGCGGAGGCCUGUGUUUGCGGCCUUCGGCAAGCGACUGAGAUGGCGAGCGCAACUGCACCUGCAGCCGCAGUCCCCACCCUGGCUUCGCCUUUGGAGCAGCUCCGGCACUUGGCGGAGGAGCUGCGGUUGCUCCUGCCUCGAGUGCGGGUCGGCGAAGCCCAGGAGACCACCGAGGAGUUUAAUCGAGAGAUGUUCUGGAGAAGACUCAAUGAGGCAGCUGUGACUGUGUCAAGGGAAGCCACGACUCUGACCAUAGUCUUCUCUCAGCUUCCACUGCCGUCUCCACAGGAAACCCAGAAGUUCUGUGAACAAGUCCAUGCUGCCAUCAAGGCAUUUAUUGCAGUGUACUAUUUGCUUCCAAAGGAUCAGGGGAUCACCCUGAGAAAGCUGGUACGGGGCGCCACCCUGGACAUCGUGGAUGGCAUGGCUCAGCUCAUGGAAGUACUUUCCGUCACUCCAACUCAGAGCCCUGAGAACAAUGACCUUAUUUCCUACAACAGUGUCUGGGUUGCGUGCCAGCAGAUGCCUCAGAUACCAAGAGAUAACAAAGCUGCAGCUCUUUUGAUGCUGACCAAGAAUGUGGAUUUUGUGAAGGAUGCACAUGAAGAAAUGGAGCAGGCUGUGGAAGAAUGUGACCCUUACUCUGGCCUCUUGAAUGAUACUGAGGAGAACAACUCUGACAACCACAAUCAUGAGGAUGAUGUGUUGGGGUUUCCCAGCAAUCAGGACUUGUAUUGGUCAGAGGACGAUCAAGAGCUCAUAAUCCCAUGCCUUGCGCUGGUGAGAGCAUCCAAAGCCUGCCUGAAGAAAAUUCGGAUGUUAGUGGCAGAGAAUGGGAAGAAGGAUCAGGUGGCACAGCUGGAUGACAUUGUGGAUAUUUCUGAUGAAAUCAGCCCUAGUGUGGAUGAUUUGGCUCUGAGCAUAUAUCCACCUAUGUGUCACCUGACCGUGCGAAUCAAUUCUGCGAAACUUGUAUCUGUUUUAAAGAAGGCACUUGAAAUUACAAAAGCAAGUCAUGUGACCCCUCAGCCAGAAGAUAGUUGGAUCCCUUUACUUAUUAAUGCCAUUGAUCAUUGCAUGAAUAGAAUCAAGGAGCUCACUCAGAGUGAACUUGAAUUAUGACUUUUCAGGCUCAUUUGUACUCUCUUCCCCUCUCAUCGUCAUGGUCAGGCUCUGAUACCUGCUUUUAAAAUGGAGCUAGAAUGCUUGCUGGAUUGAAAGGGAGUGCCUAUCUAUAUUUAGCAAGAGACACUAUUACCAAAGAUUGUUGGUUAGGCCAGAUUGACACCUAUUUAUAAACCAUAUGCGUAUAUUUUUCUGUGCUAUAUAUGAAAAAUAAUUGCAUGAUUUCUCAUUCCUGAGUCAUUUCUCAGAGAUUCCUAGGAAAGCUGCCUUAUUCUCUUUUUGCAGUAAAGUAUGUUGUUUUCAUUGUAAAGAUGUUGAUGGUCUCAAUAAAAUGCUAACUUGCCAGUGAUUAAAUGAGUGCCCUUCCAAAGUUUCUUUUUACCAGAAAUACAGUGGAUUGAGACUAGAACAUUGCUUUCAUUUGGGUUUGUAGGUUUAAAAAUCUGAUUCUAAUCAGAAGUAUAUUUAGAACAAAACACUUUAUUUAUAAAAGAUGACUCCAAAAUUCAUCUUAGUAUUUCACCAUGUUAUAUAUUAUUAUCAGCAAGUCCUUCUGAAUAUUAUCACAGAUUACUCCAUGUCUCUAAAAUAUAUUGGCAUUGAGCUCAUUUGUUAGGUUUGCCCACCUUAUUGAACAGAUUUAUUUUCCUUAUACAUACUUGUGUUGUCCUUGGUUACGUGUGUCCCCAAAUGUAAAUACCAAAUUUUUAUAAAUCAAAAAUUUUUUAGUGUGUAAGAGAUUUUAUGUAAUUUUAAGGGCCUUUUCAGUUCAUCCUUUUGCAAAACCAUCACCACUUAAUUAUACUUUUGCAUCAGUCUAGAAGACUGCAUAUUGGAAAGCAGUGUAAAUCUAUAAUGAUGUAUAUUCUGGUGAGCUGAAUAGGGCAUUAUGCAUGUCCUACAGGUCUCCGCCACCUCUCAUGCCCAUCAUCUUCCUUUUGUAGGUGUAAUUCAUAACAUAUGCCUUUCUGCUGUCUUUAGGUAUAAUCAGCAACAGCAGUCAUUCUUUGAGUGACUAAUGUAUACUUGGGGUUGGGGUUGAAAUUCCUUAAGCCAAAUGAGUUUUAGCUUACUGUUUUGAAGUGCCAUUUUGUAUUGUUAACAAGUGUCAUGAAGGGAAGGAACUAAAAUCAAACUGACAGAGUGUCAAGGCAACAAAAUAACAUAAACAAAAUAAUAACAUUGUACAACAGUCUAGUUCUUUUAUCCUUUCAUAUAGAGCCUAUUUUUUAUAUACUUUUAUAUUUCUCUACUGGACCAAAUUCAUGUUAUUAACAUCAGACUUUAAUUGUGGGAUACUUAAUGAAUAUAGAACUCUAAUAUAAAGACUUACCUCUAGCUGAAUUAUUCUCUCAGGUCCUGUAUUGUAUAACUUCGUUCAGUCAUGUUUGGAUCUUUAAGGAUAAUGAUCAGGGAAAGCACUGAUCAAUGUAAUUUUUUUUUUUUUUUUUUUUUUUUUGAGAUGGAGUCUUGCUCUGUCCCCCAAGCUGGAGUGCAGUGGCACACUCUCGGCUCACUGCAACCUCCGCCUCCCAGGUUCUCAAGCAAUUCUCUGGCUUCAGCCUCUCAAGUAGCUGGGACUACAGAUGCACACCACCAUGUCCAGCUAAUUUUUGUAUUUUUAGUAGAGAUGGGGUUUCACCAUGUUGGCCAGGCUGGUCUCAAACUCCUGACCUCAGGUGAUCUGCCCACGUCAGCCUCCCAAAGUGCUGGGAUUACAGAUGUGAGCCACCGAGCCCAGCUUGAUCAAUGUAAUUUUAAGAUUACCUAAAAAUUCCAUUUUGGGAUAAUAUCCCACUUCAUCAGAAAUAUUAGAAUGAUUUAAGUGUUAGGUCCUUUCCCUUAUCUGUAAGUUAAUGAAUGUAUUAAUGAGCAGUAAAAUGGUUGCAAAAAACCUGAACCUGAACAAUCUGAAUGUACUCCUUAAAGGUAUCUGAGCACCUUUUCAACCUGAAUGACUACUCAUUUAUCUGAUAAAGUGAUGUAGUUUGGAUAUUCAACCCUGCAAACCUCAUGCUGAAAUUGGAUUCCCAGUGUUGGAGGUGGGGCCUAAUGGGAGGUGUUUGGAUCCCUCAUGAAUGGCUUCGUUCCAUUGGUGGGGUAAUGAGUAAGUUCUCGCUCUAUAUGUCCCUCCCCCACCCCAGAGCUGGCUGUUAAAACGAGGCUGGCACCUGGCACUUACCCCUACCCCUCAACCCAUUCUUGCCCUGUGAUCUCUGCUCACGUUGCCUCCCUUCAUCUUCCUGCAUAAGUGGAAGCAGCCUGAAGCCCUCACUGUUUCUUGUACAGCCUGCAGAGCCGUGAGCCAAAUAAAGCUCUUUUCUUUUAAACUA